AGGUGGCAGCGCUUGCAGUCGGGCUACGGAGGCCGGGUUGCCAGAUUACGGGAAAGCCAUUUAAGAAGUUCCUGGAAUAAUAUUAGUCAGAGUAAUAUAGGAUCUGCAGGAAGUGUCUCAAGAUAGUUGGAAAAGAAGAAUUUCUAGACUCUUCAUCAAGAUCUUCAUUUAUACAGCUGUUAAAUCCAAGGCUACUUUGGUGAAAGCAUGAAUAAAAAUACAUCUACUGUAGUAUCACCCAGUCUACUUGAAAAGGAUCCUGCCUUUCAGAUGAUUACAAUUGCCAAGGAAACAGGCCUUGGCCUGAAGGUACUAGGAGGAAUUAACCGGAAUGAAGGCCCAUUGGUAUAUAUUCAGGAAAUUAUUCCUGGAGGAGACUGUUAUAAGGAUGGUCGUUUGAAGCCAGGAGAUCAACUUGUCUCAGUCAACAAGGAAUCUAUGAUUGGUGUAUCAUUUGAAGAAGCAAAAAGCAUAAUUACCGGAGCCAAGUUGAGGUUAGAAUCUGCUUGGGAGAUAGCAUUCAUAAGACAAAAAUCCGACAACAUUCAGCCAGAAAAUCUGUCAUGUACAUCACUUAUAGAAGCUUCAGGAGAAUAUGGACCUCAAGCCUCAACAUUAAGUCUUUUUUCUUCUCCUCCUGAAAUACUAAUCCCAAAGACCUCAUCCACUCCCAAAACAAAUAAUGACAUUUUAUCUUCUUGUGAGAUAAAAACUGGAUACAACAAAACAGUACAGAUUCCAAUUACUUCAGAAAACAGUACUGUGGGUUUGUCUAAUACAGAUGUUGCUUCUGCCUGGACUGAAAAUUAUGGGCUACAAGAAAAGAUCUCCCUAAAUCCCUCUGUUCGCUUUAAGGCAGAGAAACUGGAAAUGGCUCUAAAUUAUCUUGGUAUUCAGCCCACAAAGGAACAACACCAAGCCCUGAGACAGCAAGUACAAGCAGACUCAAAAGGGACAGUGUCUUUUGGAGAUUUUGUCCAGGUUGCCAGAAACUUGUUUUGCUUGCAGUUGGAUGAAGUAAAUGUUGGUGCACAUGAAAUUUCCAAUAUAUUAGAUUCACAGCUUCUUCCUUGUGAUUCUUCAGAAGCAGAUGAAAUGGAAAGGCUCAAGUGUGAAAGAGAUGAUGCCUUGAAAGAAGUAAAUACACUUAAGGAAAAAUUAUUGGAAUCAGAUAAGCAAAGGAAACAAUUGACAGAAGAGCUCCAGAAUGUGAAACAAGAAGCCAAAGCUGUAGUUGAAGAAACAAGAGCCCUGCGUAGUCGGAUUCAUCUUGCUGAAGCUGCUCAGAGACAGGCACAUGGAAUGGAAAUGGACUAUGAAGAAGUGAUCCGUCUGUUAGAGGCCAAGAUUACAGAGCUAAAGGCUCAGCUUGCUGAUUAUUCUGACCAAAAUAAAGAAAGUGUUCAGGAUUUAAAAAAGAGAAUCAUGGUACUCGACUGCCAAUUACGAAAAUCAGAAAUGGCUCGAAAAACUUUUGAGGCAUCCACUGAAAAGCUUCUUCAUUUUGUAGAGGCUAUUCAAGAAGUAUUUUCUGAUAAUUCUACUCCUUUAUCAAAUUUAAGUGAAAGAAGAGCUGUGUUAGCUUCUCAGACUUCCCUCACACCACUGGGAAGGAAUGGACGUAGCAUCCCAGCAACGCUGGCGCUUGAAUCUAAGGAACUUGUUAAAUCUGUUCGUGCCUUACUUGAUAUGGAUUGUUUACCUUAUGGGUGGGAGGAAGCUUACACAGCAGAUGGAAUCAAGUACUUCAUCAAAGCUUCCCAUUGCUAGAAGGAAGCCAACCCAAAAGCAUUCAGCAGGAGAGCCCAGGGGAGACAAUCUAUAGGUCUCUACUUCCUCCUGAGGCACAGACAAGAUCACAGAUGGAACUGAGAGGCAGGUGGGGAAUAAUUGGCACAGGAGUAAUCCAGUGAUUCCUGACGCAUGUGCAAGAGGAGGUCUGCUAUCUGAGAAAGAUGAGUAUGGGUGAGUAAACAAACCAUUCAUUUUUUGAUGGGUAAUUAUCGCCCACCUUCUAGGGGCACAGAUGCUGCCCAUGGAUGAGAUACACAGUUCUUAUUCUCACAGAGCUUACAGCCAGUCAAGUGAAGCAGAGAAGAAGGCAAACUCAGCACAGGGGAGGAAGUAAGUGUGACAGACGCACAUAGUGGAAGCAUGUAACUCAGGAAAGAGUGGUCUGCGAGGGCUUUUUGGAGGAAGUUAUGCCUCAACAGAAAUGUAAAUGAUUCGUAGAUAUUGACGAGGCAUGUGGAGAAGAGGAAAGGUGAGAGAGCCUCCUGAGUAAUGUCAGGGUGAUGAGACAGAGUGAUGCUGUGGGGUUCAGUGUAACCAUGUAAACAGAGCACAUCUUCAGGUGGGCAACCAGGUGGGGACAGUAGGAAUAACCUGAAAUAACUCUGGAGAAGUAAGCAGGGCUCAGAUGCCAAAAGGCCUCAUAAGCUAUGUUAAAAAAUCUGGACAUUCCCCUAAGAGUAAGGGUGAGGCACAAAAGAUCUUAAGUACGGUGUGAUCAUUAAUUUUAUGUGUCAGUUUUACUGUGUUGAGGGAUACCCAGAUAGCUAGUAAAACAUUAUUUCUAGGUGUGUCUGUGAGGGUGUUUCUGAAAAAGAUUAGCAUUUGAAUCAGUAGACCCAAUGAAGAUCUGCCCUCAGCAAUGUGGGUGAAUAUCAUCCAAUCCACUGAGGGCUUGAACAGAGCAAAGGCAGAGGAAGGGAGAAUCCUCUCUCCCUCUUCUUGAGAUGGGACAUCAUUCUUCUUCCCUCAGACAUAAUAUUUCCUGGUUUUGGGGCCUUGAGACUCAGAUUGGGCCUUCCACCAGCCCCACCCUCACCCUAUCCCCACCUCCCCACUUAGUUCUCAGGCCUCAGAAGAGAGUCUCAUCAUUGGCCCCCACCAGUUCUCAGGACAUCAGACUGGGACCAAAUUACACCCCUGCUUUCCUGGUUCUCCAGCUUACAGAGGCAUCUCCUGGAACUUCUUAGCCUCUGUCAUCACACAAACCAAUUCCCAUAAUAAAUUCCCUCUUAUCUCUGUACCUAUAAUGAUACAUAUGAAGAUACUGGUUCUGUUUCUCUGGAGAACCCUGACUGAAACACAGGGCAAUGGCAUAAUAAGAUUUGUUUUUAAAAACUCCCAGGUGUAGAGGACAGCUGGGCAAGGAACAAGAGUGGAGGAAAUUUUCAGACUGGUCCCUUCUCUGGCUGUAACACCCUGGCCAAGUGUCUCAACCUCCCUAAGCCUAGCGCCCUCACCUGUUCAACAGCAAUAAUCAGGCCUGUCUUGCCUACCUCACUAGAUUAUUGCAAGCAGUGAAGGGACGUGAACAGGCUCUGGCAACCAGAAAGCACAGUCAUAAUUCCAAAUAACAUGAUGAAAAGAAAAUGUGGCUGAUAUUGUUAAUUUCCCAAGGAAAUCUGUGUAGUCCUCUGACUCAUUUUGCAAAGACUGGAGAGGAAAUGGAGAAGGAAGCACACCAGAGCCAACACUUUGAAAGGAGGUUGUUCAUUCCAUCACUUUCGAAAUGGAGAUUCUGUCCUCCUGGCUGUGUGGCACAUGAUUGCUGUCCAAUAAACAGGAAUUGAUGAAUGGCUGAGUGAGGCUUUGUUUUGUUUUCAUUUUUCAAACUCUUAUGACUGCAGAGGGGAAAACUAAAUCAAUGCCAUAUGCCUGUAAAAAUCCCUCUGACAUCUUUUAUUGUAAUGGAAGAUGACAAUGGUUAUCAGAGCAGAAGGAACAUGCCUGAGUGAAAGUAAAUACCAAACACCUUUUGGGAAACAAAGCACCUCCUGGUGACCUUUGCAGCUGUUCCACUCCCUAAAUUAUGGCAACCUGGAGUUGUCUAAUGACAGUCUAACCAGGAUUUCCUCUUGUUUUCAAAUGUGUGCGUCCUCCCUCUCCCUGGGUUGUGCAGAAUUUUAAAUGUCACAGUAAUCACAUUUUUCCCGAGGAUAACAUGAAAUAUCAUUGGAGCUUAAUGGAGAUGAACAAAUGAUCAAAUUCAGAUGUUGGUGAUAUAUCAUGUUAGAGGAAUGAGAUCUAUUCCACAAGCUGCAAAGCCUCUAAAUUUUGUUAACACAAAUAAGAAAUAAAGUAGCAAAAGCUACUAUUUCUGAGUCCCUACCAUGCACCCCACCCUGUUCCAAGUACUUUACACCUAUCAUCUCAUUUAAUCCUGACGGUUCUUCAGCGUGGGCAUUAUUGUCCCCAUUUAACACAUAAAUUCAGAUAAAUUCAUUGAACUAUUUAAAGCCACAUGGCAUGUGGUUUUGUGAAUGUCCCCCAUUCAAGCUAUAUGGCCUUAAUAAAGUUACUUACCUGCUGUCAGCCUCAUCUGCAGAAUGCAAAUAUCAAAGACCUCUCACUCAUAAGAUUGUGAAGGAUUACAUUAAAUAAGUUAUGUGUAGCACUUAAGUACAGUGCCUGCUAUACUGCAAUCACUUACUGUAUUAGUCAGAAUUCUCCAGAGAACCAAUAGGAGAUAUAUAGAUUUGUUUUAUACAUAUAAGGAGAUUUAUUGUAAGGAAUUGGUUCACAUGAUUAAAGAGGCUGUGAAUUCCCAUGACCUGCUAUCUGCAAGCUACAGUAGACUCCAAAGAGCUAGUGGUAUAGUGUCAGUAUGAGUCUGAAGGCCUAAGAACCAGGACAGCUGAGGUCCAGUUCAAGUGCAGGAGAAGAUCAAUGUUCCAGCUCAAAAACAGAGAGAAAGAAAUCUUUCUUACUCAGCUUUUAUUCAUCCAGACCUUCAAUGGAGGAAGAGGCCUAACCCAUACUGGGGAGGAAAAUCUGUUUUACUCAUUCUAUCCAUUCAAAUAUUAAUCUCACCCAGAAAUACCCUCACAGACACACCCAGAAAUGUUUAAUAGGAUAUCUGGGCACUCUGUGCCCCAGUCAAGUUGACAUAUAAAAUCACACUAAAUAGUGCCUUAUUAGCAAUAUUAUUGUGAUUGUUAUUAUUGUAGAUCUGGUAUUUUACAUCUGUCUAGCCCUUUCCACAUUGCCCGAAACCAAAACCAAUCAUCAGUAUAAUCAUAAUGAAAUCAAAGCUACAUAUAAUUUUUUUCUUCCCUUAGGAAAUUUUUCAACAUCUUGCACAUUUAAUUCAUGGCAAGAGUUACUACCACUGGGACUAUUUAAUACUCUUGGGGAAAAGUGGAAAUAUAUGAUAGCAAUUCAGAAAUAAAGGAAUGUCUCAUAUUGAUUCCUAGAGCAUGGAAAAAAAAAUAAAGGAGGGGGCCUAAUUAACAGCUUCUUGCCAACCCUUCAGACUAGACCUGUGAGUAUAGGUAACCAAGCAAAGAAGAGCUUAGACCAUGAACUAAAAGAAAGCACAUCCUUGGGCUGCAGGCAUCUCAUUAGACUCUCCUAUAUAAAACUGAACAAAAAUGAGUUCAAAUCUGAAGGCAAAAAGCUAUAUACAGUUGAUCCUUGAACAACAUGAAUUUGAACUGCAUGGGUCCACAUAUACAUGGAUUUUCUCCUACUUCUGCUACCCAUGAGAUAGCAAGACCAACCCCUCCUUUUCCUCCUCUUCCUCUUCCUCUCCCUAUUCAAUAUGAAGAUGAUGAAGAUGAAGAUCUUUAUUAUGAUCCACUUCCACUUAAUGAGUAGUAAAUGUAUUUUAUCUUAUGAUUUUCUUAAUGUUUUCUUUUCUCUAGCUUAUUUUGUUGUAAGAAUAUAGUAUAAACUAUAUGUUACAUACAAAAUAUGUGUUAAUCAACUUUAUGUUAUCAGUGUGUUAUUAUCAGACUCAAAAGUUAUAUGUGGAUUUCUGACUGCAGCAGUGUGGCGAGAUUGGCACCCCUAACACUAGCAUCAUUCAAGGGUCAACUGUAUAUAUCUAUACCACAAAAUAUUCCAUGGAAUUUUCCUUGACUCAAACCGAUAUCUCAUUUACUAAGGUGCCCACUUUCUACCCACCACCUCCAUGUCUGGUGGUGGAGUGAGAAAGAGCUGAGCUUGACAUGAAGCCCUGCCACAUACUAGCUUUGUUACCUUGAGCUAAAUACUCAUCUCUGAGCUGCAGGUGCCUCCUCCAUUGGGCACAAAACCAACUCAACAGAGUCAUUAUGAAGGUUAAGGAGGUGCCUGGCUCUAUGUCUGGCACAUGAUAAGACCGUCGUAAAUGUGAGCUUUCUUCCACUCUCUUCCUCUCACCUCCAUAAGGAAAAAGUAGUAAUAUUUUCUUAAAUAGCUACUGUUUGGGGACAACUGAAAGAUGCCAUUUGUUCUUCUUUGCAUAAGGAGAAACCUAGAACUAAAAGAACUAUAGGAACUUUCAAGUCCACUGGUCAUCAAACGAUACUCUGUGAAGCCUUGUUGGGGAGUUUGAGGUUGGGUGAGAUUUCUGUCCCUGUUCACCCCUACACUUCAACCUGAGUUCUUUUUACUUGCUUUAUGUAUGUAUUUAAGACCUUGCUUUAACAAAGGAAUCCCCAGAAAAUAAUUGCAAACCACCAGUCUAAAGAAUUACAAUUUAGAGAUGAGGAAAUGGAGACUUUACAGGUAAGGCAACCAACUCUACAAUCAUUUGAAACAGAAUCAGAAUUGAAAGGCUGGUUUCUGAACUCUGAGACCACCAUGCUUUCUGUCAUUAAGCUGUAACACCUCACUAUUACCAGUGUGGGAACAAUAAUGUGAUAUGACAGAAAGCCUCCCUCAUCACAGAGAAACUUAGGUUUGGCUCAGGUUUACUGAGGGGAGUUUCCCAUGAAGAGACUUAAGACAAGAGGAAAGACCAUUUUAGGCAUAUCUCAGAGGUCAAGGUGGAUAGCACCUGCUCUGUAUGGCCUAUAGAAGUCAAAAUUCCUUUUAGAUUCCUAUUCCAAGACUUCAUCCUACAUCAUGUCAACUGACACAAAACAAUCCAUUUUUUACUUUCUGCUACAAGAGCUGAGUAUACUUCAAUUCACUAACAUUUGGGGGAAUGGAGGUGGAGACAGAUGCAGGUUCACUUUGCUAAACUCAUAACAUUACUCUAUCACACUAGCAACCUAUGCUUCUUAACCUUUCACCUUUGUUUCUUCUCAGCUCCUUCAUCUGAUUGUCACAUAAGACUCUAAAUUCUUCUGCUACUUUGCAGACUUAUCUAGUUUUUCUACCAUUCUUGAAUAUUCAGAACUACCAAGGUGCUUAGCAAUUUGAAAAAGUCCUCAUGCUAUCAAUAAUCAGCCUUCUUAGAAUGUAGUUGUAAUUAUAGGUACAAAUUUUUUAAAUAAAUCUUAAAUUAAAUUGUAUUCUAUUAUAGGAAAAACAGAGUCACCUAUGAUACAAUGAGAGGAUAAAGCAGUAAUGCUGAAUUUUUCCUACUCAAAUUUCACCUUCCCUUUGGAGUGCUGUCACAAUUCUUUUGCUGAUAUCUCAUUCAGGCCCUGGAAAAUGUUAUUUUCACCUUAAAAUUCACAGCCCAAGCCUGAACUGCAUCCCUCUCCUUGGUUCCCAUAAGAAGCACAGAGAAAGGGAAAUUUAAUUUUUAAGAUAAUUAAAUAGCAUCUGAAAUGGUGGACUAAGUAGUUCAAACCAACACUCCCACUGAAGACAAUUAGAAAAUCCGGACUUAAAAAUAAUCGCUAAAGUCAUUGGAAAGCUGAAAAGGCAAUGAGAAAUGCUAAGACUGAUAUCUGAAAGAAGAUGGAAACCAAUAGAGAUAAGUUAAACAUUUGAGCCUAUUUACCCUUAGGGUAUCUGCUGAUUCUAGAAGGGGUGAGUAAGGGUAUGAGUUACUGAACAGAAAUUUUAACAGAUUCAUUAGCGUUAAAGAGACAAAAGUAGGAGGAGUCCAGAGCCCACCAAAGGGGUACUGAUAAAUCUUUGGAACUUUAAAGGCUCAACAUCCUAUGAGUAAGGGUAAAGUGGAAGAUUAACCCUUGCAGAAACUGAAGACAAGAUUAAAAUCAUUUCAGUCCCUGAAACUGGAUCAAUAUAACUCAAAGAUUCUAGUGCCCCUACUUAUCUUCCAUAAAUAAACACAAAUUAUCUUUUUCUUUUUUCUUAAUUUUCAUACUACCAUAUCCAGCAGGUGGUAAAAAGAAACCAAGCACAUGAGAAGACAAGGCAAGAAUCAAGAGAAAACAGCAAAAAGAGAGUUCUAGAUAAUGGAAUUAUUAGUCACAAACUUUAGCAAUUCUUAUAAAGGAGAUAAAAGACGAAAUUCGAGAUUUUGGCAGAUAAUUGGAAACCACAGAAAAGGGGAUACUUUAGAGCUAAAAGAUAUAACCAAAAUUAAGAACUCCAUGAUGUGUUUAACAGCAGUUAGGCACAACUUAAAACAGGGAAAUGGAAGAAAACAUCCAGAAUUAUGCAAGAAGGAACAAAAGAAUAAAAAUACAGAAGAGACUAAAGGGCAUAUGAAGUACAGUGAGAAUAUGAAGUACAAUGAGAAGGGAUAACGUAUAAUUUGAGUCUCAGAAUAUACAGAGGGAAAUAAUGGGUUAGAAAAAAUAUUUGAAUAUACAUUGACUGAAUUCUUACCAAAACUGAUGUAAUAUAUUAAGCCAUAAAUUCAAGAGUGCUUACAAACCCCAAGUAGGAUAAAUACAAAGAAAGCCACAUCUAGACACAUCAUAGUAAAACUUCUAAUAAACAAAGACAAAAAGAAAAUAUUGAAAGCAGACAGAAAAAAAAAGACCACUUACCAUGUCAACAGAAAUAAUAAGAGACAAAAAACAAUAGAAUUACUCCUACAAAGUGCUAAGGAAAACAACAACAACAACAAAAAACAUUGCCAACUUAGAAUUCUAUGUCUGGCAAUAAUGGCUUUUAAGAACAAAGAUAAAAUGAAAACUUUUUUAGACAACAAAAGUCAAGAGAAUUGAAGAGACCCAUGUUAAAGGAAGUUUUUAAGAAACAAGUUACUCCAAAUGAAGCUUAAAGAUGAAAGAAAGAAUAAAAAUCAAAUAAAAGAAUAAAUAUGUGAUUAGAGUUCAAUGAAUAUUGACUGUAAAAAGCAAUAAUGAUUACAUCUCAUAGAGUUUUAAAUAUCUCUAAACCUAUUGAUAGGCAGCAACAAUAGCAUAUAAGUCAAAAGGAGGGUAGACUUCAAAUAUUCUAAUGUCCUUGCACUUUACAUAAAGAGGGUAAAAACUACCAAGCAGCAUUAGCCUUUAAUGGGUAAUGGAUGAAUGUUGUAAUCUCUCAAUCAACCACCAUAAAGUUAGUAAAAGUAAAAAAAUGGAAAAUUCAACUAACAUAAAAUAAGACAAGAGGCUAGGCACAGUGGCUCAUGCCUGUAAACCCAGCACUUUAGGAGGCUGAGGUGGGAGGAUUGCUUGAGCCCAGGAGUUCAAGACCAGCCCGGGCAAGACAGCAAGACCCAGUCUCUAUAAAAAAUAAAUAAUAAAUAAGAAGACAAGAAACAAGAAAUAUGUACAUACAUUGGUUGGCAUAAGUAGAAAGCUCAUGUUAAAAUGACAGAUUCAAGCCAAAUAUAUCAGCAAUUGAUUAAAUGUAACUGGACUAAAUGCCUCAAUUGUAGGCAAAGAUUGUCAGACUUUAUAAUUCAACAAAGGUCAACUAUAACUGUGACUCUUGUUCACAAGAGUCAUUUCAACAUGGAGAUAUUGUAAAAGGAUAUAAAAAGCAAAUGAAUUUUAAGAGAUAUACAGUGCAAAGAAAAACUGAAAGAAAGGUAGUAUCACUAAAUUAACAGAGAAAAGUAUACUUGAAGGCCAAAAUUGUCACAAAUGAAUAAAAGAGAAACUUCAUAAUAAAAAAUGGUUUAAUUUGCCAGGUAGCUGUGGCAAUUAUACAUUUAUGUGAACCAAAUAAUAUACAAGCUUAUGUUAUUAUUUCAAUAUCUCACUAAGAGUUUUUCAUCAUACCUUGCAGUAUAAGCAGACAAAAAUAAUCAGAAAAAGUUAUGGACAAUCUGAACAACACAUUUAUAAAUGUGACUUAAUUGUUAUCCUACUUAACAACUGUAAAAUACACUUUUUUUUUCAAAUACACAUGAAGUAGUUAUAAAACUUGACCAUAUUCUGGGUCAUAACACAAUUCUCAACCAAUGUCAAAGAACUGAAAUCACCUCAUCUGACAAAUGAUGAUUUUAUUUCUUCCUUUAUAAUUGUAUAACUUUUAUUACUUUUUCUAGCCUUAUUAAGUUGCUUAGUGAAUUAUUGAAAAGAGGUUGUAGAGGGCAAGUUUGUUACAUUCCCAAUCUCAAAGAGAAAAUGUGACAUAUUAUUUAUAACCAGAAGAGAAAUUUAAUUUUUACUAUUUUUUAAAAAGUUAUUAUCAUAAUGUAUAACACAUGCACAAGUGUACCAAAUAUAAAUAUGCCAUUCAGUGAAUCAUCACAAAGAAAACACUUGUAUAAGCAUCACACAGGAGAAAUAGAACUUUCUAGCACCCUUGAAGUCCCCUUGAGCUCUUCCUUUUCUCCAAGGUAACCAGUAUCCUAACUUCUGAAAGUAUGUAUUCCUUUCGUGUGCUUUUAAACUUUAUGUAGAUGGAAUCAUACAUAUGUAUUCUUUUACCUGGCUUUAAAAAACUCAUUGCAACAUCAGAAAAAUAUAAGCUGAGGAGUAUUCUUUAAAGUAAUCUCUAGUCUUCAAGUGUGUUAACAUCAUAAACGUCAGGGGAAAACUGAGGAAUUAUUCCAGAGCAAAGGAAGCUAAAGAGACCUAACUAAUAAAUGUUUUCUUGGAUUAGCUCCUGGACCUAUGCAGAUAUUAUUGGAACAAUAGGCAAAAAUUGAAGGGGGUCUGUGGAUUAGAUGGUAUUAUUGUACUAAUGUUAAUUUCUAGAUUUUGGUGAUACUUUGGUUGUAUGAAAGAUUGUUUGUUUGUUUGUUGAGAUGGGGUCUCGCUCUGUCACCCAGGCUGAGUGCCGUGGUACCAUCACAGCUCACUGCAGCCUUGACCUCCUGGGCCCGAGCCAUCCUGCCACCUCAGCCUCCUGAGUAGCUGGGAUACAGGCGCAUGCCACCAGGCCAGGAUAAUUUUUGUAUUUUUUGUAGAGAUGAGGUCUUGCUUCAUUGCUGAGGCUGGUCUAGAACUCCUGGGCUCAAAUAAUCUGCCCAUCUCGGCCUCCCAAGGUGCUGGAAUUACAGGCAUGAACCACCACCUGGCCACUAUUUUCUUCUUCUUCUUUUUCUUCUUCUUCUUCUUCUUCUUCUUCUUCUUCUUCUUCUUCUUCUUCUUCUUCUUCUUCUCCUUCUCCUUCUCCUUCUCCUUCUCCUUCUCCUUCUCCUUCUCCUUCUCCUUCUCCUUCUCCUUCUCCUUCUCCUUCUCCUCCUCCUCCUCCUCCUCCUUCUCCUCCUCCUUCUCCUUCUUCUUCUUCUUCUCAUACUGAAGUAUUACAAAGCCAUGGGGCAUUAUGUGUGCAACUUGCUCUCAAGUGGGGUGUGUGUACGUGUGUGUGUGUGCACAUAGAGAGGAAAAGAGAAUAGAAAUUAUAAGGUACAUGAAGUAAAAUGUUAAUAAGGAAUCUCUGUGGAGAAUAUAUGAGGUCUUUAUAUUAUUUCAAAAUGAAAAUGAAAAUAAAGCAUUAUAACAUGAGCAACUUCCAAUGGUAUUAAAAAUUCACCUGCCUUCAAGGUGUUCAUAGUCAAAGACCGGAGUGGAGAGAGCAGAUGAGUACUGGGCAGUGACAUCUGAGGACAACUACUCUGAUAGGGCAAAGCACUUACUGUGUGUGCCAGGACCACAGAGGAGACAGACUCAACGCAUCCACUCAGGGCAUGGAGGCUUCCUCACAGAAUUAAUGGUUGACCCAAGCCUUACAGGAGGUCAUAAUCUGGAGAAAGACGAAAAGGGUGAACUGAGCAGAGGAACGUCAUGUUUAAAGGCACGGAGAAAGGAGAGAAUCUGGUGAGUUUGGGAAGCUGUAAAUGGCUGUCCAUGGCUGGGACCCAGGAUCCAUGUGUGGAGGCACCAGAGCAUGAAGCAGCCUGGACUUUAUCCUGAAGAUGAUGGUGCAUAACAGGGUGUUAGAUCUAGAGUGGACAUAACAAUUACUACGCCAACCCCUUCCAUAUAUCCUCUGUGAAACAGAGCUUUUACCACCACUAUGCAAUUACUUGUCUACAAACCCUCCACGUGAUUGCUGACACUGAACCAUACAUUAAUUUAUGACCACAAAUAUAAAUGAAAAAAUUAGCUUGGGAUAAAUGCAAUUUUUUUUGAGACAGGAUCUCGCUCUCUCACCCAUCCUGCAGUGCAUAAAUGCAUUUAAAUAGUGAAUGCCAUAAAAAGAAAUUUUCAGGAGGAAAACAAUGCAUGGAAAGAAAAGCUCUAGCUAUAUUUCAAGUUAACAAAUACGGAAAAAGCGAUCUUAAGAAUUAAUAGCCUCAUUAUAUAUUAAUACUUCUAAAACUAAGCAAAUUUGAAAAAACUUGGUUGGCUUUGUUUAGUAAAUCAAAGUAUGUAGUGUUGUAAAAGAAUAGGCAUUUAAAGAAAAUAUAUCUUUACUAAAAUCCAAAUGGGGAAAAUAUGCAAUGCACCAAAUUCUAAAGGAUGUAUGAUGGUUCAAUCAAAGGAACAUGGAAGUUACAAGGCAGCUGAGUUGAAGAUCAAAAAUGAAUUCUUGGCUUAGAGAAGAGGUAAUAAAAUGACAAAAUCAUUUUAUCUGUGAUGUGGUGCAUGGUCUUUGGAGACAGACAAAUGUGGAGAGGAAUACACAAGGUCUCUGUGAUCUUUUGCCAGUUGAUUAUCCAGUUGUCAUGAAGGCUAAAUGACAAAUAGAUAUACUAUCAUUAGUCCCCAAUAAAUAUCACUCCCUUUCUCAUUUUCUCCAUUCAUUCCUCUUUCCUCCAUUUCACAGCUAUAUCCUUAUUUUCACACAUGACCAACAAAAGAGACAGCAAGCAAAACAAAGAUCCUCCAAAAUUACCUUAAAAGACCCAAAAUAAAAAGAGCUCACUCUUCAAAUCAAAAGGGACAAAGAAACCAUGAAAGGUAUUCAUUCAAGUGAGGCUUAGAGGCUGUGGGGCGAAGAAAUACACGGAUGUCCAGAGCUGCCUUAUGCAGACAGAGUAUUUUGCAAAUCUGUUCCAGGCGUCUGCUGAGGUUUCUGCCUCCUUCAGGGAAUGUAUUGCCGUCAUUAAUGCACACUGACUGGUAUGCUUUCCCUCCAACUGGUUUUGCAGAGAAGUAGGCAGCAUGCACCCUCAUAGGCAAGAUGCAAAAGGAGAGCAGAGAGGCAGGAUGUCCAUGUAUAUGCAGAAACCUUGCCCAGAAGAUGACUUAUUACAUUAAAGGUGAUCAAGCUUGGGAAGGAACCAUGAAAACUCUAUUAUGCUGUUAGGAAUAUUCACAGCCAAGUAUGUGAUAAACUGCACCCCUCCCUUGUUUCUUGCCAAACAGGCUGAUGUGCUGUGCUGCUUAUGAUUUAAAAAAAAAAAAACAACAACAACAGUGUUCUAUGGAGCCCAUUCUUAGAAUGCCAAAGAUCAUGACAAGUCCCAGAUCUUCUGAGCCAACCCAAACCUGGCUGGUCUCAGAGAUGGAUGAUAUAGCAUCCUGGAGCUGGCCCAGUGUUCCUCUCCAAAUGGAUUCAGGAAAUGCACUGAGCGCUGACAAAGCUUCCUCCCAAGGUUGUGAGGCUGUAAUGAGAACACAUCCGAAUUUCCCCCCAGGGAGGCUGCCAAGAACUCAGAGGAGUGGGGAAGGAGUGUCUGGACCACGGGAUGGCUGUGAGGGAGAUAAGCUCCAGCCCUCUAGAGUUGUCGAUCAGGGAUUUAGAGGGACUUAGAGAGAAUGAAAGCACUCAGAGAAAUAAACCUUUCAUAACCAUCUUUAGGGCAGGCAGACAUAAGAAUUAAAGAGUAACAAAGAUCUUUGCUCUGACAGAAGAGCCCAGAAAGCUUAAACCAUAGCAACCUUGGUAAUAAGUGUACCAGAUGCUAUGCCGAACUCUACAUGCAUUAUCUCAUUUAAUCUUCAUGAUGUCCCUGUGAUUGGCACUGUUAUCAUAUCCAUUUUACAGAUGAGGAAACUGCACCUUAGAGAGGUUAUGCAACUAAUCUAAGACCAACAGCAGUGAGUUUUGAAACCAUCACUAGAUACUGCCUCUCCAUUGAAGAUAAUCUAUUGCCUAACAAGGUGUUUAGCACACUGUAAGCAUUCGGUAAAUAAUUAUUAAUGAAAUAAAUAAUCAACUAAUGUUGAAUAUGGCAGAAUAAGGUCAGCACUGGAUUAAUGAAGACCUGCACUAACUGGCUGUGUAACUCACGGUAAGUUGCUGGAUGUGUCUGGGUCACAUUGUCCUCAUCUGAAAAGAAGAAUUUAGACUAUAUGCUCCCUGGGAAAUAUGGCAUGAUGAAUAAGUCAUAUGGAGAGCCAGCAUUUAAAAGAACCCAUGCAUCAAGUCUAAACCAGAGUCCCCAUUGUAAUUCUGACCCAUGUUCCAGCUAUCUGAAAUUGCUUCUCUCUCCCUAGAACAGUGAUACCUGGGAACUGGACAGACACGCACCUCUUUCUCUCCAGAGCACCUUAUGGAAUAGUAGCAGAGGGCACUGCCACUAACAGAAGGGCCCUUUAUUAGAGCUGCCAUUCCAUUCUCAGUGACUGCAUUCUCCUCUUUGUCUCACUCAAAAAGCACUGUGGCCACUCCUGAUUUUAAAGGAUCCCACAAAGAAUUUUCUUACCCUGGUUCCUGGCAAUUGAAGUGCAGAGAUCCUUUCUACCAAAGUGAUUCCAUAAUGACAGCAACCAUCUAUUAGAAUGGUCUCAGAGCAAAACUAUGUUCUUAAAUGCUUUCCGAGUUUCCUCUUCUUUCCGUUAAAAUUUCUUUUUGUCAUUAAAAGGCAUUAAGUAAGAGCUUGGGCAGAACUUGCUGAACUGCAGAAUUGGUUGCUUUUGUAUCAAUUCUUACUGUACCCAGACAUUAUCCGUAUUUCAUUCUUUUUUUAGUCACUGUCUGCUUCCAGACCUGUUCAUUCUCCUCAUCUACCCAGUCUCCAUCAAAGCCUGCCACCUCUGGGAAGACUUUUCUGAGUCCCUCAAGCAGAUGUGGGCACUUUUUGUAGGAAUGAAUUAUACUUGAGGCUAGAAUCCAUGAUUUCUCCCCUUUGCGUGCUCAGUACCCAGCAGAAGGCCUGAUGCAAGGGGGACAUAGAAUAUAUAUUUGGCAAAAAAAAUGCUGAAAGGAUGCUUCAAAAAACCAAGUAAAACAUUAAUAGAUUAAAUGAAAAGUAAAUUAUGAGAAUAUAUAUUUUUUAGUAAUGGUUAUCAAAGAGUCUACAUCCAGACAAUAAUUACACUGAUGACCACUUUUCCUCUUUAGACUUUAUAAAAUGUGUGACUUGAACAAGCCCUGUGUAAGUUGAAGCUAAGGACAGAUAGUUUAUCUAAGAGAGAGAAAGAUGGAUUUUCUGAAAAUCCAAAUGCAUUUGCAUCAGAGCUUACUUUGAGCCUUAACCCAGUUCCAACAAAUGGAUGAAAGGAUCAACCUUUCCAUCAACAAGCAUCUACAAGAAACAGGCUGCCCAUCACUGCCCUAGAUCUCAGAGACGAAGUGAGGCCACGGUCAAGUUACGUGCCCCAGAUGGAAGGAGACAGUUUAGUCUGAAAGAGUGAAGGCUGAGUUAUGAAGUAAUUCUUGUUGAAAAUAAACCUAUACAAGUAAUUAAAUUUGGAAUAUCAGUCCUCUCUGACAUUGGCCAGUUCUGUGGCCCUAUUCAAACAAGAUUACGCUCUGAAAAACAGAUGCUAGACGAAAAAUAUGAGAAAGUAUAAGAGUCAUCUAUGUGCUACCCAGGUGGUGUGAUUCAGUGGGAAGAGUGACUGUAAAUUGGAUUAAACCUGGGUUAGAAUCCUAGCCUUGCCCCACAGUACCUCUUAGUCAUGCCACUUACCUUCUGAACAUCAUUCUCCUCUCUAGAAGAGUAGAGAAAAUAACACUUAUUAUAUAUUGUUGAAAGUAGGCAGUUCAGUAAGUGUUACUUUCCUUUCCUCUAGGCAGUAGGCCACUGGAGAAAAGAAUUGAUAGGGAAACUUUCUAAACGGGGAAAAAAUUGGCUAGAUUUCCAAGUGGGGAAAUUUUACUGUUGGGAUAAUUUGGUUUUAGAAAGGAAUACUGAAGGUAGGAAUCCUCAAGAAUUGGAAUCUCUAGUGAAUCACUUUAAUUCUACAAAUACUUAUUGAACACCAUAAUGUGACAGGUAUUGUCCUGAACCCAAGGAUACAGCAAGGAACAGAACAAUCCCUGCCCUCAGAGAGCUCACAAGCUCUCAGGAAAGAUAUUCAUUAAAUGUCUGCAUGUGUGAUGAGCAUUUUGAAAGGGUUCCAGGGAAGCAUAGGGGUGCACAAGACCUCAUGUAUACUGUCAAGGAUGGCCUUAUCUGAGAAAGAUUCGUUGAUGCUAAUAAUGAAUGAAUAAGUAGGGAUACAAUGGUCAAUUUCACAUUCCCCACCACCACUAUUCAUAUGCCACAGAUAUGUCUGACAUUCCUGCUACAUGCCAAGCCCUGAAGAGACAGAGAUAAAAGAGAAACUAUAAAGUCUGUGAUCUCCCAAGGCCUCAAACCCCACAGAAGAACAAAAGUAAUUGCAUAGAUGCCAAAUAAUAUCAUAAAUAAAGGGUUUUGAAAACAAAGGAAGGAAUGGUGGAUCUGCUCCCGAGGGAGAUAAUAAGCAUGCCAAGGAGGAGAUCCAGCAUUGUGGUUUGGGUGGCAAUUUCCACGCUACUCCCUGAGCUUUUACACUGUGUAUAUAAGUGAGACCUGCAGUGCCAGCUGGUAUUGUUAACAACUCAAGGCAUUAAUGUAAUACAGUGAUGCCCUCAGAAAAAAAAUAGAGCUGAUAAAGAAAUUAACGUGUUCAAAAAUACACACUUCAUCUGCUGACUUGCUCACAUUUCCUUCACACAUGGUGGGGUUUACUCAGAGCCAGAGAGAAUGACCGUAGCAGUAAAGUGAAACUCACAAGUGAUAGUCAGGGGAAAGGCCAAUCCCCACCCUAGCCUCAUUUACUGAGCAACUGGAGAGCUUCCAUUUUCAGAGCCCUUUCCAGUCUUCAAAGUAUCUUCAUAUUCCAAUUUUAUUGGUUCUUCCCAACAAAUCCUAAAACAAGGAGUGCAGAUCUUUUAUUCCCAUUAUACAGAUGAGGAAGCUGAAACUCAGGGUAGAUAGGUUCUUUCUAGAGUCAUGUGGCUGGAGAGUGCUGAAGGGACUAUUAGAACCCAAGUCUGAUUUUCGCUUUACUGAUCUAAUACCCCAGGACAGGGCUUCUCAAACUACAAUGUGCAUAUGUGCCACCUGGGAGCCAAUAUGCAGAAUCUGAUUCAUAAGUCCGGGGUGGGACCUGAGAUUCUGCAUUUCCAGCUCUGUGACACCAGCUGGAGAAAACGCAUUCUUCCUGAUGAAAGAUAAUCAUAGUCUGUGUUUCCCAGAUGAAAUUUCUUCAAAUGGUUAUGACAAUGGAGGAUCCUUCUUAUUUUUUCAAAAUACCAAAUAGUGGUCCCUCAACAACUUCAACCUAAGCAAUACUUAUUUCCCUGACACUUCAGGGGACAUAGACGUCUUCUGUUAUAGUUCAUCUGUCUCUGUUCUCAUCCCCAUCUCUCUUAGUCUCUUUCUGCAUCUACCUCAGUCUCUGACUCUUUUUCUAUUACUCUUUCUCAUACUUGACCACCAAACUAUGUCCUUGAAUGUACAGUGUCAAGUUGAGGUGUUCUCCGAUACCAACAAUCAAUUCUCUGAUUCUCCAGGCACUAACUCAAGAUAUCCAGCAAUUCAAUUCAAUUCUCACACUGCUCAGAGAUAGUGCAGAUCCCACAGCUUAAGAGCUCAGUCAAACAAGGCUUCCCCCAAUUUCAGGCACCAGUCAAAAAUCCCAGGCCCCCUGUAUUUCUGACUGAUUGGUUACAAAUUGUACGUUUCCACAACAUCUUUCUUAUGCUUGAUAAUUUGCUAGAACAGUUCACCCAACUCAGGAAAGUGCUUUACUUACUAUUAGCAGUUUAUUAUAAAGGAUAUAACUCAAGAACAGCUAAAUGGAAGUGACAAAUAGGGCUAGGGAUUGUGCUAUAUAAGUUUGUGAAUUAUGUAAUUUAAUCAUAACCAAAACCAAAAGAAAUACGUGCUAUUGAAUCCAAUAAAAAAUUCUGUCUGUCUGA